GUGGAUGCUCUCAGCUGGCUGGCGGGAAGAUUUUACUCCCGAGUAGCGGAAAGAUCUGCUCGAGGCCUGGGUGCUUUGGUGUCGGAGAUCCGAGAGUCGGAGAUCGGAGAGUCGGACACAGGACAGUCGGACACCGGACAGUCAAACACCGGAGAGUUAGACCGGGCUUCUCGGUGGGGAGAGGCUCUGGGAUAACUACUGUUACAGCUUUGAAGGGUCAAGGGUGUGCGCUUUUUGUUUCAUCCUUCCCUUUCCUGCUGCAGGGCGAGGCCGGUCUGUAGCGGAUCACUUCCUUUCGCCCACACAUUGGCGGAGGAGAAACCGGAAAGUUAAUCACUGCCCUGCUCUGAGAACUCGGGCCUUUAGGGGCACGUUCGCCUGCUGACCGGUCUUCUGAUCUCCCCAUUCUUUUCCAUGCAGGAGGAUUGGCCACCAAAGCCUGUUUAUUAGCAGCUGCCAUUUGUUGAAAGAAAUUUGGAUUAUUUUAGAAACAAAUUUGGAAAGAAAAAGAAUGGCGUCCGUUUCAGCUCUAACUGAGGAACUGGAUUCUAUAACCAGUGAGCUACAUGCAGUAGAAAUUCAAAUUCAAGAACUUACGGAAAGGCAACAAGAGCUUAUUCAGAAAAAAAAAGUCCUGACAAAGAAAAUAAAGCAGUGUUUAGAGGAUUCUGAUGCCGGGGCAAGCAAUGAAUAUGAUUCUUCACCUGCCGCUUGGAAUAAAGAAGAUUUUCCAUGGUCUGGUAAAGUUAAAGAUAUUCUGCAAAAUGUCUUUAAACUGGAAAAGUUCAGACCACUUCAGCUUGAAACUAUUAACGUAACAAUGGCUGGAAAGGAGGUAUUUCUUGUUAUGCCUACAGGAGGUGGAAAGAGCUUAUGUUACCAGUUACCAGCAUUAUGUUCAGAUGGUUUUACACUCGUCAUUUGCCCAUUGAUCUCUCUUAUGGAAGACCAAUUAAUGGUUUUAAAACAAUUAGGAAUUUCAGCAACCAUGUUAAAUGCUUCUAGUUCUAAGGAGCAUGUUAAAUGGGUUCAUGCUGAAAUGGUAAAUAAAAACUCCGAGUUAAAGCUGAUUUAUGUGACUCCAGAGAAAAUUGCAAAAAGCAAAAUGUUUAUGUCAAGACUAGAGAAAGCCUAUGAAGCAAGGAGAUUUACUCGAAUUGCUGUGGAUGAAGUUCACUGCUGUAGUCAGUGGGGACAUGAUUUCAGACCUGAUUAUAAGGCACUUGGUAUCUUAAAGCGGCAGUUCCCUAACGCAUCACUAAUUGGGCUGACUGCAACUGCAACAAAUCACGUUUUGACGGAUGCUCAGAAAAUUUUGUGCAUUGAAAAGUGUUUUACUUUUACAGCUUCUUUUAAUAGGCCAAAUCUAUAUUAUGAGGUUCGGCAGAAGCCCUCAAACACUGAAGAUUUUAUUGAGGAUAUUGUAAAGCUCAUUAAUGGGAGAUACAAAGGGCAAUCAGGAAUCAUAUAUUGUUUUUCUCAGAAAGACUCUGAACAAGUUACGGUUAGUUUGCAGAAUCUGGGAAUUCAUGCAGGUGCUUACCAUGCCAAUUUGGAGCCAGAAGAUAAGACCACAGUUCAUAGAAAAUGGUCAGCCAAUGAAAUUCAGGUAGUAGUGGCAACUGUUGCAUUUGGUAUGGGAAUUGAUAAGCCAGAUGUGAGGUUUGUUAUCCAUCAUUCAAUGAGUAAAUCCAUGGAAAAUUAUUACCAAGAGAGUGGACGUGCAGGUCGAGAUGACAUGAAAGCAGACUGUAUUUUGUACUACGGCUUUGGAGAUAUAUUCAGAAUAAGUUCAAUGGUGGUGAUGGAAAAUGUGGGACAGCAGAAGCUUUAUGAGAUGGUAUCAUACUGUCAAAACAUAAGCAAAUGUCGUCGUGUGUUGAUGGCUCAACAUUUUGAUGAAGUAUGGAACUCAGAAGCAUGUAACAAAAUGUGCGAUAACUGCUGUAAAGACAGUGCAUUUGAAAGAAAGAACAUAACAGAGUACUGCAGAGAUCUAAUCAAGAUCCUGAAGCAGGCAGAGGAACUGAAUGAAAAACUCACUCCAUUGAAACUGAUUGAUUCUUGGAUGGGAAAGGGUGCAGCAAAACUGAGAGUAGCAGGUGUUGUGGCUCCCACACUUCCUCGUGAAGAUCUGGAGAAGAUUAUUGCACACUUUCUAAUACAGCAGUAUCUUAAAGAAGACUACAGUUUUACAGCUUAUGCUACCAUUUCGUAUUUGAAAAUAGGACCUAAAGCUAAUCUUCUGAACAAUGAGGCACAUGCUAUUACUAUGCAAGUGACAAAGUCCACGCAGAACUCUUUCAGGGCUGAAUCGUCUCAAACUUGUCAUUCUGAACAAGGUGAUAAAAAGAUGGAGGAAAAAAAUUCAGGCAACUUCCAGAAGAAGGCUGCAAACAUGCUUCAGCAAUCUGGUUCUAAGAAUACAGGAGCUAAGAAAAGAAAAAUCGAUGAUGCCUGAUAUGAAUGUUACUAAAUUUUCUAAUUAAAGAUGGUUUAUGCAUGUAUAUGCCAUUAUUUUUGUAGUUAGACAAUAGUUUUUAAAAGAAUUUCAUAGAUAUUUUAUAUGUAUGGAUCUAUAUUUUCAGAGCUUAUCUCUGAAGAUCUAAACUUUUGAGAAUGUUUGAAAAUUAGAGAUCAUGAAUUAUAUAAUUUUCCAGUAUAAAACAAGGGAAAAAUUUUUAUGUAAAACCCUUUAAAUGUAAAAUAUUUGAGAAUAAGUUCAUACAAUCGUCUUAAGUUUUUUAUGCCUUUAUAUACUUAGCUAUAUUUUUUCUUUUGACAUAACUAUCUUUUUGAAAGCAAUAUUAUACUGACAGAGGCUCACUGAGUGAUACUUUAAGUUAAAUAUGUAGAUCAAGGAUGUCCAAUCUUUUGGCUUCCCUGAGCCACAUUGGAAGAAGAAUUGUCUUGGGCCGCACAUAAAAUAUGCUAACACUGAUGAUAGCUGAUGAGCUUAAAAAAAAAAUUGCAAGAAAAAUCUCAUGUUUUAAGAAAGUUUACAAAAAAUGUAAAAUAUUUGAGAAUAAGUUCAUGUAAUUGUCUUAAGUUUUUUAUGCCUUUAUAUACUUAGCUAUAUUUUUUCUUUUGACAUAACCAUCUUUUUGAAAGCAAUAUUAUACUGACAGAGGUUCACUGAGUGAUACUUUAAGUUAAAUAUGUAGAUCAGGGAUGUCCAAUCUUUUGGCUUCCCUGAGCCACAUUGGAAGAAGAAUUGUCUUGGGCCGCACAUAAAAUAUGCUAACACUGACGAUAGCUGAUGAGCUUAAAAAAAAAAAAAUUGCAAGAAAAAUCUCAUGUUUUAAGAAAGUUUACAGAUUUGUGUUGGGCUGCAUUCAAAGCUGUUCUGGGCUGCAUUAGACCCGUGGGCUAGAGUUGGACAAGCUUGUAGAUGAUUUCAGGUUAUAAAACCAGAAGUACAAUUCAACAAAAAAGGAGUAAGUCAUCAAUAUAAAUAUUAGCAAACGAGAUAUUGCUACAUCUCUAUUUAAAGUAAAAUACAACCGAUUUUAAAGUUCCUGAAACCAUAGCCAUAUUUUGACAUUUCACAAAGAAUGGUUCUAGUCUACUAGAGUACAUUUGGCUAAGUAGAUAACUUACCUAAAUUUGCUCCAAAGCUAAAUCACAAGUAAACAUAUUUAUGUUUAAAACACAGAAAUAAAUAACUUAAGAUUUUUAUCUAAGCGGUCAGUGUUGUAUUGGAAAGAUAUAUCUAUAAAUAAACUUUGAACUGAUUUCAAACUUA